GUUACUUUGUUGGAAGUGGAGAGUGGAGGGUCAGAAGGGAGUGGACCAGUUCAGGUCCCAGAGGGAAUCCUCCCUCCCUCUGAGCCGUCUUUCUUCUCCUCCCUAUUUCGCAGAUAUCCCGAGAUUAGGUCCCCAGCUUCCAAAGAGAGGAUCAGAAUGUCUCAGGAUAAUGACACAUUGAUGAGAGACAUCCUGGGGCAUGAGCUCGCUGCUAUGAGGCUGCAGAAGCUGGAACAGCAGCGGCGGCUGUUUGAAAAGAAGCAGCGACAGAAGCGCCAGGAGCUCCUCAUGGUUCAGGCCAAUCCUGACGCUUCCCCGUGGCUUUGGCGCUCUUGUCUGCGGGAGGAGCGCCUUUUAGGUGACAGAGGCCUUGGGAACCCUUUCCUCCGGAAGAAAGUGUCAGAGGCACAUCUGCCCUCUGGCAUCCACAGUGCCCUGGGCACCGUGAGCUGUGGUGGAGACGGCAGGGGCGAGCGCGGCCUCCCGACACCGCGGACAGAAGCAGUGUUCAGGAAUCUCGGUCUCCAGUCCCCUUUCUUAUCCUGGCUCCCAGACAAUUCCGAUGCAGAAUUGGAGGAAGUCUCCGUGGAGAAUGGUUCCGUCUCUCCCCCACCUUUUAAACAGUCUCCGAGAAUCCGACGCAAGGGUUGGCAAGCCCACCAACGACCUGGGACCCGUGCAGAGGGUGAGAGUGACUCCCAGGAUAUGGGAGAUGCACACAAGUCACCCAAUAUGGGACCAAACCCUGGAAUGGAUGGUGACUGUGUAUAUGAAAACUUGGCCUUCCAAAAGGAAGAAGACUUGGAAAAGAAGAGAGAGGCCUCUGAGUCUACAGGGACGAACUCCUCAGCAGCACACAACGAAGAGUUGUCCAAGGCCCUGAAAGGCGAGGGUGGCACGGACAGCGACCAUAUGAGGCACGAAGCCUCCUUGGCAAUCCGCUCCCCCUGCCCUGGGCUGGAGGAGGACAUGGAAGCCUACGUGCUGCGGCCAGCGCUCCCGGGCACCAUGAUGCAGUGCUACCUCACCCGUGACAAGCACGGCGUGGACAAGGGCUUGUUCCCCCUCUACUACCUCUACCUGGAGACCUCUGACAGCCUGCAGCGCUUCCUCCUGGCUGGGCGAAAGAGAAGAAGGAGCAAAACUUCUAAUUACCUCAUCUCCCUGGAUCCUACACACCUAUCUCGGGACGGGGACAAUUUCGUGGGCAAAGUCAGAUCCAAUGUCUUCAGCACCAAGUUCACCAUCUUUGACAAUGGGGUGAAUCCUGACCGGGAGCAUUUAACCAGGAAUACUGCCCGGAUCAGACAGGAGCUGGGGGCUGUGUGUUAUGAGCCCAACGUCUUAGGAUACCUGGGGCCUCGGAAAAUGACUGUGAUUCUCCCAGGAACCAACAGCCAGAACCAGCGAAUCAAUGUCCAGCCACUAAAUGAACAGGAGUCGCUACUGAGUCGUUACCAACGUGGGGACAAACAAGGGUUGCUUUUGUUGCACAACAAAACCCCGUCGUGGGACAAGGAGAACGGUGUCUACACGCUCAAUUUCCAUGGUCGAGUCACUCGGGCUUCGGUGAAGAACUUCCAAAUCGUGGAUCCCAAACACCAAGAACAUCUGGUGCUCCAGUUCGGCCGAGUGGGCCCAGACACAUUCACCAUGGACUUCUGCUUUCCAUUUAGCCCGCUCCAGGCCUUCAGCAUCUGCUUGUCCAGUUUCAAUUAGAAGCUGGCUGUUGAAUAACUCAAUAAAAUACCAUACCCUUGCCA